GCCCAGAAGUGGAAUAAUUCAGGAAAGUGCAGGUUCUGGGAAGUCUCGGUGGGUUCCCCGCAAAAUCAGAGAUGGCAUCUCACUAUGUUGCCCAGGCUGAUCUUGAACUCCUGACCUCAAGUGAUCCUCUCUCCUUGGCCUCCUAAAGUGCUGGGAUUCCAGGUGUGAGCCACUUCACCCAGCCACAUUUAUCCAUCUUGUAAAAUAUUGCUUUGUUUUUUGGUGCAUUUCAAACCCACAGGUCCUGACUUCAGGAGCAAGACACUUCAAGUGAGGUGAGGAGGAGGUUCCAGGACCUGGAUACCAUCCUUUGCAGGGAUGUAAUUCACCAGAGACCAAGAUUUCUAGCCAGAAAUUGAGGGCAGCUCAAGGAGAGACUACAGACACAGCAUCCUACUUACUGGCUAUUUCCCAGUAACAAAAGAAAAUGAUCAAGUCCCAGGAAUCACUGACCCUGGAGGAUGUGGCUGUGGAGUUCACUUGGGAGGAGUGGCAGCUCCUCGGCCCUGCUCAGAAGGACCUGUACCGAGACGUGAUGUUGGAGAACUAUAGCAACCUCGUGUCAGUGGGGUAUCAAGCCAGCAAACCAGAUGCACUCUUCAAGUUGGAACAAGGAGAGCCAUGGACAGUAGAAAAUGAAAUCCACAGCCAAAUCUGUCCAGAAAUCAAGAAAGUUGACAAUCAUCUACAGAUGCACUCACAAAAGCAAAGAUGUCUGAAGAGAGUGGAACAAUGCCAUAAACAUAAUGCAUUUGGAAACAUCAUUCAUCAGAGGAAAAGUGAUUUUCCUUUAAGGCAAAAUCAUGAUACAUUUGACUUACAUGGGAAAAUACUGAAAUCAAAUUUAAGUUUAGUCAACCAGAACAAAAGGUAUGAAAUCAAGAAUUCUGUGGGGGUUAAUGGAGAUGGGAAAUCCUUCCUUCAUGCCAAGCAUGAACAAUUUCAUAAUGAAAUGAACUUCCCCGAAGGUGGAAAUUCUGUGAAUACAAAUUCACAAUUCAUUAAGCAUCAGCGAACUCAAAACAUAGAUAAACCCCAUGUAUGCACUGAGUGUGGGAAGGCUUUCCUCAAGAAGUCUCGCCUCAUCUAUCAUCAGAGAGUUCACACUGGGGAGAAACCUCAUGGAUGCAGUAUAUGUGGGAAAGCCUUCUCCAGAAAGUCCGGGCUCACUGAACACCAGAGAAACCACACAGGAGAGAAACCCUAUGAAUGCACUGAAUGUGACAAAGCAUUCCGCUGGAAAUCACAGCUCAAUGCACACCAGAAAAUUCAUACAGGAGAGAAGUCAUAUAUAUGCAGUGAUUGUGGAAAAGGCUUCAUCAAGAAGUCUCGGCUCAUUAAUCAUCAGAGAGUUCAUACAGGAGAGAAACCACAUGGAUGCAGCCUGUGUGGGAAGGCCUUCUCCAAAAGGUCCAGGCUCACUGAACACCAGAGAACUCAUACAGGAGAGAAACCCUAUGAAUGCACUGAAUGUGACAAAGCAUUCCGCUGGAAAUCACAGCUCAAUGCACAUCAGAAAGCUCACACAGGAGAGAAGUCAUAUAUAUGCCGUGAUUGUGGAAAAGGCUUCAUUCAGAAGGGAAAUCUCAUUGUACAUCAGCGAAUUCAUACUGGAGAAAAACCCUAUAUAUGCAAUGAAUGUGGAAAAGGCUUCAUCCAAAAGGGCAACCUCCUUAUUCAUCGACGUACUCACACUGGAGAGAAACCCUAUGUAUGCAAUGAAUGUGGGAAAGGCUUCAGCCAGAAGACAUGUUUAAUAUCCCAUCAGAGAUUUCACACAGGAAAGACACCCUUUGUAUGUACUGAGUGUGGAAAAUCCUGCUCACACAAGUCAGGUCUCAUUAACCACCAGAGAAUUCACACAGGAGAGAAACCCUAUACAUGCAGUGACUGUGGGAAAGCUUUCAGAGAUAAAUCAUGUCUCAACAGACAUCGGAGAACUCAUACAGGGGAGAGACCGUAUGGAUGCUCUGAUUGUGGGAAAGCUUUCUCCCACUUGUCAUGCCUUGUUUAUCAUAAGGGAAUGCUGCAUGCAAGAGAGAAAUGUGUAGGUUCAGUCAAAUUGGAAAAUCCUUGCUCAGAGAGUCAUAGCUUAUCACAUACACGUGAUCUCAUACAGGAUAAAGACUCUGUUAACAUGGUGACUCUGCAGAUGCCUUCUGUGGCAGCUCAGACCUCAUUAACUAACAGUGCGUUCCAAGCAGAGAGCAAAGUAGCCAUUGUGAGCCAGCCUGUUGCCAGAAGUUCAGUCUCAGCAGAUAGUAGAAUUUGCACAGAAUAAAAACCAUAUGAAUGCAGUGAAUGUGGUAGUGCUUUCAGUGAUCAAUUACAUCAUAUGUCACAAAAAACACAGAGGAACAAACUGAUAUAUUCAAGGUGGAAAGCCCUUGAAUAAAACCUUAUGGCUAAUAAGCAUAUACUCAGAGAAAAAUAGUAUGAAGUGGAGACUGGGAAAUUCUUUUAUGGGAAGAUAGAUCUUCUCAUCAGUGACCAUAGAUCACAUCUUCAGUGAGCUUAUAGUUGGUAGAAAUAUAAUGAUCAUGGAAAAGUCCUUGUUCAGAAACAGUACGCCAGUAGGUAUCAGGGGGUUUACACAGGAGAGAAACUUUUGGAAGACCUUUGAAGGCUAUGAAUGUGGCAGGGUUGCUAGUGGUACAUUCUGCCUUAUCCUCAGAGGGAAUCAUAUAGAAAUAAAACUAUGAAAAUGUAACUAGAACAUCUUCAUCAAAAUAUGAAAGAACACACGAAGCAAAUAAGCCCUGUGAAAAGGAGUAUUUUAGAGAUUUCGAUCAGAAAUCUAACAUCAUUAUAUGGCAGAUAAUAUACAGGAUGUGUAUUUUAGGACAAUAUACCUUGAAUCACUAGUUGAUAUGUCAAUGACUAAUUAAAAGGGGUUGUCAGUGUUACACAUCAUUGGUUAAAUUUAUAGCACAAUGUACCUCUUCCCCCUUUUUUGAUAAGAGUCUUCUAUUCCCAACCAAGAUCAUUAUAUGAUUAGCUCUUGUGUUUCUUUGAUUCCAAAUUUCUUCACUUGUUAUUUCAGACUACUGAAGCUCUUCAAAAGGAAAAAUGUAUUUAAUUUAAUAAUGUAACACAACAAGUUUGGAUGUGUUUAACUUUAUAAAUAAUCACCCCAGAGGAAUGAAGUUCAAAACUUGUGAAUAA